AGAGUAUGAGGAAGCCAGCACUAGUCAAGUGACUCUAAGAAGGGCCAUUUUCCCUUGUUGUCUUUGAAAAUACUUCAUUUUCUUAGCAUUUCAGGAGAUUAUAACAUCCUGUAUUUCAGUUUCUGAGAGCUUUACUGACUGAUUUCCCUAUUCAAAACAAUCCUCAUUUCCUACAUUUCUGAAGAUCUCAAGAUCUGGACUACUGUUGAAGAAAUUCCCAGUAAGGCUCACUUAUAUCUUUAGAGAUGGCAAAUAACUACAAGAAAAUUGUUCUACUGAAAGGAUUAGAGGUCAUCAAUGAUUAUCAUUUUAGAAUUGUUAAGUCCUUACUGAGUAACGAUUUAAAACUUAAUCCAAAAAUGAAAGAAGAGUAUGACAAAAUUCAGAUUGCUGACUUGAUGGAGGAAAAGUUCCCAGGUGAUGCCGGUUUGGGCAAACUAAUAGAAUUCUUCAAAGAAAUACCAACACUGGGAGACCUUGCUGAAACUCUUAAAAGAGAAAAGUUAAAAGUUGCAAAUAAAAUUGAAUCCAUUCCAGUCAAAGGAAUAAUCCCAUCUAAAAAGACGAAACAGAAAGAAGUGUAUCCUGCUACACCUGCAUGCACCCCAAGCAACCGUCUCACAGCUAAAGGAGCAGAGGAGACUCUUGGACCUCAGAAAAGAAAAAAACCAUCUGAAGAAGAGACUGGAACCAAAAGGAGUAAGAUGUCCAAAGAGCAGACUCGGCCUUCCUGCUCUGCAGGAGCCAGCACGUCCACAGCCAUGGGCCGUUCCCCACCUCCCCAGACCUCAUCAUCAGCUCCACCCAACACUUCCUCAACUGAGAGCCUAAAACCAUUGGCCAACCGUCACGCAACUGCCAGUAAAAAUAUUUUCCGAGAAGACCCAAUAAUCGCGAUGGUACUAAAUGCAACAAAAGUAUUUAAAUAUGAAUCCUCAGAAAAUGAGCAAAGAAGAAUGUUUCAUGCUACAGUGGCUACGCAGACACAGUUCUUUCAUGUGAAGGUUUUAAACAUCAACUUGAAGAGGAAAUUCAUUAAAAAGAGAAUCAUCAUUAUAUCAAAUUAUUCCAAACGUAAUAGUCUCCUAGAGGUGAAUGAAGCCUCUUCUGUAUCUGAAGCUGGUCCUGACCAAACGUUUGAGGUUCCAAAGGACAUCAUCAGAAGAGCAAAGAAAAUUCCGAAGAUCAAUAUUCUUCACAAACAAACUUCAGGAUAUAUUGUAUAUGGAUUAUUUAUGCUACAUACGAAAAUUGUAAAUAGGAAGACGACAAUCUAUGAAAUUCAGGAUAAAACAGGAAGUAUGGCUGUAGUAGGAAAAGGAGAAUGCCACAAUAUCCCCUGUGAAAAAGGAGAUAAGCUUCGACUCUUCUGCUUUCGACUGAGAAAGAGGGAAAAUAUGUCAAAACUGAUGUCAGAAAUGCAUAGUUUCAUCCAGAUACAGAAAAAUACAAACCAGAGAAGCCAUGACUCCAGGAGCAUGGCACUACCCCAGGAACAGAGUCAGCAUCCAAAACCUUCAGAGGCCAGCACAACCCUACCUGAAAGCCAUCUCAAGACUCCUCAGAUGCCACCAACAACCCCAUCCAGCAGUUCCUUCACCAAGAAGGAUGAAACCCACCCAGGAGCACAGUCAUCGCCUGCAAACUUUAGAAUCACCUCACCAACUGUGGCCCCUCCUCUUUCUUCUGACACUUCCACCAACCGCCAUCCAGCAGUUCCUUAAAUAAGGAAGAUUACUGUUUUUCAUUGGUGCAAAUAUGGUGUAUGUGAGGAGGUAUCCAGACAAGGAGAGAUGAAUACAACAGUAUGUUCGUACCUUCUAUUCCAGUUUCCUUUCACAAUUUUCCACUACGACUAAUGACCAUAACUUAGGAUUGAUAUUCAAAAUCCCUGUUUCUUUCCAUAGCUAGUGUCUUGGCAUAUGCUACUUCCUUUUUUUAGAAUCCCUUACUCUCAUCUCUUCAUUUGCCCCAAUAUAUUUCUGGGCCAACCAAAAUCCCCCUUCCUCAGAAAAAUACUGCACUGAUAUUCUCCUCCUGCCAUAGAACACAUCAUGCCAAGGUGUCCUGAACAUUUCUCUUUAUUUUAUUUAGAACAUUUAUUAAAAUUCUAAUAAUAAAGUGUUUUUCAACCACACUUGAUAAUAAGUACAGUUUAUAGAUUUCUUGUCCAGAGAACAUCAGACAAAGGUGAACUAAUGAAUUUAUAUCUAAGUGUUCCAAUUGAAUCCCAGCCUGCUUUUGGUCAUGAUAUGACCAGUGGAGUCACCUCCACCUAGGGAACAGAAGACUAUGAUCUACAGUGAGAGGGAAGGUGAUGAAAGAGAAAGGCAAGAGGAGAAUCAUGUCACCACUCUUUUAGUUGAAGACAUGUCACCAUACAGACUAGUUGAAGACAGAUUACCUAUAUACAGGAGUUCUCAAUUUGUGGUCGUUUUUUGGUUUGUUUAUGUUUUUGUUGUUUUUGAUAAGCCCGAGAAUCACAUUUUCCUCAAUAAAUUAUAUGUAAUUUAUUUGAGAGUCAAAGCUAGCACGUCCUCUUUAGCCAUCUUGGCUUAGGUGACCAUGGAUGGAACGCAUAUGUAGUCAUUACCAGCUCAGACCCACUUUUCUGUUACUUAAUAGACAUAAUUGAACAUCCCAGGACAACAUUCUGGAAAAGAACUUAUUUUUCCUGCAUUUUGGCUUUGAAGGGACUACGCAAAGUUUGCCUAGGUUCUACCAUUUUAAAUACGCAUUAUGGUCUGUUUCUAUAGCCGUUAGAUUUAUUUGACUGCAUCUAAACCUCCCUUAGCCCAGGAAUCUCAGCUAGGGUCCUAUGUCUCCUACACCUAACCUCCCAUAUAGCCAUUUCUUCUUUGAUAUCUAGCACUUCCACAGGAUGCCUGGAAAAUACAUCCUGUUACUUCCUCUGUGAUUCACUAGCUCUGAAAGAAGUCCUUGCUUUUGUAUAUCAUAGAUCAUCCCAAUAAUACUGUGUUUGUAUUAAUUAUUAAUUUGUAUAAAUUUUUCUAUGCUUUUGGAUUUAAAGUCAAAAGCAGACCAUUCUUAUUUUUCAUCUUUUGUCAUGACUCUCCUAAAUCAAAGAGCCCAGAAUGGUUGGGAAAACAAAUGGAGAUAUUACUGGCUCAGAAUUACUAUAUGGGAAAAAACGAAGCUAUUAGUUUUAUUCCCAAUCACUACAACUUUAUCUGGGUUUUCCACAAGAGGAUCAACAUAAAUCAUAAUUCAUUUCUGGAUCAGGCUGACAUAAAAAACUUGCAUAGUCUUUAAAUAACAAUGAAAACAAUAUUUUUCUAACUGAGCUUCUACUGGGUAAAGCUGGAAGUGAAAGUUAUGUUUUUAUGUAUAUGAUUGCAUUUACUCUUCAAUACACCUCUUAUGAGCACAGUAGAAAGACCAUGUUCCAGGGAAAAAACGUGUUCUGCUCUAGACAAGUUAAGUUUGAGAUUCCCACAGGACAUCUAAGAAUUAUCCAUCUGAUAUAUAGAGCUUAAACUUGGGUAAUUUUGGCUGGGCCUUUUACUGAAUUACAUCAAUAGAGACAUAGUUGUUAAAACAGUGGAUGUGACUAAAAGUACCUAAUAGAAUGGAAAUAAUGAUGUCUCUCAUUUACUGAGUAUGCAGAAUGACUCAGACUAUUCUAAGGGUUUUUCAAUAAUUAUCUUCAUUAAUCCUUUAUAAUCCAAUUGUUUCACAUAUUAGCUCAUUCAAUUAUUUGUGGUACACAAUGAACAGAAGAGGGAGUUAAAUUUGAGGGUGGCCAACAUACCUCAUAACAGUCCUAAAUUACCAAGGAUGUCCCUAAGCAAAUCAGAACACAAAGGUAGCUGUCUUUUGUGAGAAACAUCUCUGUGUAGACAGAGAUGGUUGGAUCUACAUGACAAAGUUUAUGCUGUUUGUCACAUAUAUUCAUGUGGGAUUCUUGGAACAAAUAAAGGCUAAUAUUGGAAUGCAAAAAGAUCAGAAUAAAGGCUAACACAUUCAGACACACAAAAAUGCAAAGGCUUUCUGAUUGCUCCAGUUCUCAGGGCCAUUAGUCAAAAGUCCCAAGCCUUCCUUGACAGCAGUUGCACCAGGAAUACAUUUUGUACGCUCCUCCUACCUUUCUGCCCAAUGAGAAGUUUCCCUUUAGCCCUUGUCGUUGGACACACCAGCUCCUUUCUCUAUCUUAUUGUUCCCUGACAUCUCCUGCCCUUUCACGUGGGCUCAUGCUGGGUAGGAGUGAAUAUCGCAUUUCAUGGUCCCAACAGAGGGGGAAGAUGUGACUCCAAGGACAGGAUUCAUUAAAGGAGAUAGAUGAGAAUGAGAAAAGAGUGCUUCAGAUGGAAAUAGAAGAAGAGAUGUGGCUCACAGGGAGGAGAGGCAGUGUGAUUGAAGAAAGAAAUGUAUGACUCCCUGCAUCUCAACGGGUUUAUUUUUAUCUCUUUAUGC